CCUGGAACUUAAAAGAAAAUUAAAUUAAUUUUUGUUAAAAAGAACUAAUUGCCUAAGCUUCAAAGCAUUCUACAAAAUAUUUAUUUCCACCACAAAGCAGAUUAAUAUAUAUAUAGCCAGUUCUUAUAAGUGUCAUUGUAAACAUUUCCAAAAGAACAGUGUUCCAAAGUCUAUGGAAAGAGAACUCUACCAUUGUGUAAGAGACUUCUUGUGGCAUUAGUGCUAUUUUAAAUCUAGAAUUAAAACAAGGCUUUGAAAGGAAAAGCCAGCACCAUCAGUUUUCAGGGACAAUAGGGACAUACUCUAGAGGACUUCAGUGAGGACUCCAAGACAGAAGAGAGCUGCUAGAAACAGCAUGUGCUGAUUGAAGUUGAGAGUUCAGAGUAAGAGGUAAGGGUCUGAGAGUCACAGUUCAAAUGCUCCUUGGACCUUCUAUUACAAAUGGAACUAGGGACUCAUGAGAAUGAUUAGAUUGAAUUGUAAUUUUUCUGUUAAUGCACAUCUGUGAGCUCCUAAGUAAGGGAUUGAAUUUCAUUCUUCUUAAUAAAUCUCUACCCAUGUACCUAGCACACAGGCUGCUAUAUGGGAGGUACCUAAUACAUAUUGAUUCAACUGAACUGAUAGGCCUGCCAGGAGGAAAACUUUUUUUUUUCUGAAGAGUGUGAGGUUCCCAGUAUCCUUGAAUAAGGCCUAAAAGAGCAAAUCAUUAAGACCGACUCAUCAAAAGAUCAGCCAGCUUUGGUCCCAAAAUCUAAAAUCAAAGAGAGUGCCACAAUUUUCCAUCGCCCUGAAGGUAUUCCAGCACUCAGCAGGGGCCAGUAAUUUGAACAAGGGGACCACUUCAAGCCUGCAAUACUGCAAUUUUUCUAACACUGAUGUGUGUAAUUUUGGCCACAGUUUAACACAGGAUAACAAAUAAAAGCAAUAUUCUAUUUGUCUAUAGUUGUUUACAUAACACCAUAGACUAUAAGCUUUUUUAUGAAAUUGUAUUUACUGUGCAUACUUUACCUAAAUUAACUAAGCAUUCCUCCUCUGCAAUAUCAUCUGCACAGGGCUAAAUUCUCCAUUAGAAGUCUUAGGCACACUGCCCAGAGCUUAUGGUACCUUGAGGGCUUCCCAAAAAUGAUUUAAUUUCUUCUAAAAAUCAGAAAAAGAUAAACUUUUAGAUUAAAGAAGAUAUUUAAAUAAAGAAGAAAAUAUACUCACCUUUAUACUAAUGUAAUCAUAAGAUAUAAUUUUAACUUGGCAAGGCAGGGAGCAGGAUUCAUAAAGGAAAACAUCAUAAAAGUCAUAACUGGACCUCAUAACCACAUAUGCCAAGAUGUGUCAAAUUUGGUGUCAUAAAGUAGAUAAUCUUAAAAAUCCUGUUUUCAGAAAAGAAUCACUCAAUUUGUCAUAGAUGGAUGGAUUGUUGUUACAUACACAGAGACAAAAUUGGGCGUUGGGACGGGAUGGUUGGGGAGGCAUGAGAUGGGUGAGCUGAGUUGGAAGGAACAACAAUCCUCCAUGUUUUAUGGCUGUGACCCUCAUUUCCCCUCUCACUAGCGGACUGCUCUAGCUAAUUAGCAAAUCAAAAGAAAUAGAAACAAUUCUAGACCUCAGCACAAUCAAAUUAGUGGAGUUAUUCGAGGAUAUCAUUUUCACACAGUGCAAUCAUGCUCUCUUUGUUUUGGUCAAACGAGUGAAAAUUAUCUUUCAAACCCAACGCCCUUCCCUCUACCCAACUGGCUCUGUGGAUAGUGGCAUUUCCUAUCUGCUCUCAUAAGUUUUACAGAUGAUCUUUUUCUAUUAAGACAGGAAUGUGCAAUGCACAAUUAAACAAUACCCAACAAGCUUCCCUUUUAAAAAUACAUUUGACUUUUAAGGUGAUUCAGCAGUAAGAGCCAUUAGUACCUCAUCUAAAUCAGGACUUGGAAAGUUUAUUAAAAUUGGAUUUUUAACCUGAUCCCAAUUUCCUUUGUGGAUAAAGAGUCCCACUGGAGUCUUUAAUAUUCAUGCUAUUAACCUGAAAGAUUCAAACAGCCAUGAUGGGAAGAAAGGCUAUACAGGGCUGCCCACUAGACUGGGGGUUACAAAUAAAACCCCAUUGAGUCUGAGCAGGUAGACUACUGUGGAUUCUGGACAUCUUCAAAAGAAGCAACUUCUCUCUUUUUCUCUCUCUCCCCUUUUCCUGACCUCCCGUCUCCUAUUACAUAUUUUGUGGGAAAGAGAAAAACCAGAAAAAUAGCAAACAUAAGCAUAUUACUUAAUUACAUAGAGCACUAGACUAGGAGUCUAGUUUUUACUGGAAGGGUAGCUUCCUCCUCUAGUGCUCUAAUGAAAUCCCUCAAUUAUAAAAUAGGGAAGUCUGGGCUAAUAAUCUCUAAUAUUGGUUGAGAAGAUGCACUUUGGAGUCAGGUGAGAACUCUUUGAAUAUCAGCCCUACCACUUAUUAGUAUGUCACCUUGAACGAGUCACUAAACUCUCCUAAACCUCCGUUUCCCCAUUUGUAAAAUGAACAAAAGGUGCAGCUCCUAUGAUUCAUUUUGCAUAGUACCUGGCACUAUAAGCCUUAGAUACACUUUAGCUGGUAUUAUUACUGAUUAUUGCCCAAACUCAUAGGUCAGUUGCUUUUGUUUCUAUUUCAUGCCUUUUCACUCCUUGAGCCUUUAUCUUCUUUAGAACAGUUUACAACUGUGUUAACUCAUGUCUGUGCGUGUCUGUAAAGGUAGGCUAGGAGUGUUUGCCUUGUUUUUCCUUGAGAUAAGAUUUUAUGCUCUCUUAGGGCAAUGGAGAUAUCUUAUUUUUUCAUCUCUCUCUUAGUAACUGGCAUAGUGUUGUACACAUACUAGGUGCUCAAUAAAGACUUCGAGAUCUUAAAAUAUUAGCAGUACAGAGAUCUUCCACUAAAACCCUCUCAUUUUUCAGUUGUUGGAACUGAUAAAAAGAGUCUUGGGCCACACAACUGACUGACAGACACUUUUGCAGUCAACUACUACUGUGUCUCCUAACAGCCUCUAUUCUCAUGCCCACGGCUUUGAAAGGGAAACAUGUUUGACUUAAACCCUGACUCCUUGAGGGAAGUUCCAUUUACAAAGUUUUUUUUUUUUUUUUUUAAGAGCAUAGUAUGUUUCAGAUACCAUGCAGGAUUGUAGGAUUCUGGGAUUCAGAUACCAUGGAGGAUUCAUCAUUAAAUCACGAUACCCAAGCUCAAGGCGUUUAUAAUCUAUUAGAGAAGACAGAUCCCUAAAUAGAUGUUUCAAUAAUGUGAUUGUGUUGUCAUAGGAGAGCUAAGCUCUGGCACUACAUGAGCUUCUGGAUAAGAAACCUAACUCAUGACCAGAAGACUUCAGGGAGAGCUAUUUAGGAGCAGUGGCAAAUGCCUGGACAUACACAUAAAACUAAGUAAGAACAAAAUAGCCAGUUGGUGUUUUUAUUUAUCUGAAUGUAAGAACAUAGAUUAUCGAUCAAUGAACAAUUGCUCAGAUUUAAAAAGAAAUGAGGAAAACUAAAAUGUUAGUCCUCAAAUUCCUGUCACUUCCCACAUGUGCCCUGCAGUCAUUUCCUGCAAAUGGAAACUUCCAACAAAAUCUCUGGGCUGGAGACCUGGGGUUCCAGUUUCUUUCAAGGUCUUGUGGUAGGGAACUAAGUGGGUGAGUAACCUGCCUUUGGCUUCCAGGGUGCAAACAGAAUCAUUGCUAACCCCCUUUGUGUCUCACAAUGGGUAAUGAAAUUCAUACUAUGGCACCAAAGCACUUUGAGCUCUUUAGAAAAAGUAAUCAUACCAACUUAGAGCAUUAAAACCACCCCGUAUUUUGAAGGACUCAUGAUCUGCACUGUGCUUGGCUGCUGGUGGAAGCUUAAAGACACCAGUAAUUGGCAGAACUUUAUCUUAGACUUCCAUUUGACCCUCACAACCUCACACAUGAUUUUACACAGCUUCCUAUAAUGGGGGAGAAAAGCCCUUCUUUUAAAUCUAAUGUUAGUUUAAAUGCUAAGGCUUUCAAAGUGGGCCUUUAAAGUCACUUUUUAGAAUUUGUAUUUUUUUUUAACCUAAAAUAGACAUGCCAACAUUAUUCUGACUAAAAGAAGUAGACAAGGUCAUUCAACUCCUAAAAGCUUAUUUUCCAAAAGCACAGUUAGGUCUCAGCUUUCAGGGUGCUUCUGGCUGUAUCAAAAAGACAGAAUAUACUGGUCACUGUGUUGUUUUCUGAAAGUGCCGAGGGUAAUCUGUGUAUGAGUUAAAGGGCCAAUUUCCUAUAGGAACCUUCUCUUAGAUGGGAUUUUUUUUUAAUUAAACAAUGUUGGUGAAAUAUAUUUAAACGUAAAUCACAAAUUCGAAGUCUUCCAAAUAUUUAUUUACUAAUGUGGAAGACAUGGAAACUACAGUAAUCUCAUUUAAAGGAAGUUACUUUGAUGUGCAUUUGCUUUUGGCGGGGUAUGAUUGCUGACCUGCCUUUGAGGGCAACUUCCUUUGGCUCAGGUAAGCAGGCAAACCCGUUUCUCCAAGGCGAUUCCAACCCCACGCCCCUCAAAACCUUAAAUCUUAAAUUGAGUUAUUGGGUGCAGGUCCUUUCUCCCACAGAACCUCCCAGCUUCCGGAAUAGAGGAGCGGGGCAGAAAUAUCCUGCUUUUUAUUUCAGAGCUGACGUUUGCAAUCCUAGUGCACUAGCGGAAAAAAAAAAAAAAAAAAAAAAAAAAAAAAGCUGAAUUUUCCGCGCUCUCCUGGCAAAUUGGCGUCCGCUCUCCGACGCUAAACCAAAGGAAAAGGAGUGUUCAAUGGCGACAGGGCGCUCUUUGAAGCCGGCUCCUCACGCGGAUUCUGGCCCAGGCCGCCGCUCCGGUCCCAGUCCGGCUGCAGAGCGAAUUGGAGAGGAUGGCACCUCCUGCUUCCCGGGGGGCGGAAGGAGCGCCAGCGCCUAAGUAAUUGAAGGCCUGAAACGCCCAUGUGCCACUGACUAGGAGGCUUCCCUGCUGCGGCACUUCAUGACCCAGCGGCGCGCGGCCCAGUGAAGCCACCGUGGUGUCCAGCAUGGCCGCGCUGCUCCUGGGCGCGGUGCUGCUGGUGGCCCAGCCCCAGCUAGUGCCUUCCCGCCCCGCCGAGCUAGGCCAGCAGGAGCUUCUGCGGAAAGCGGGGACCCUCCAGGAUGACGUCCGCGAUGGCGUGGCCCCAAACGGCUCUGCCCAGCAGUUGCCGCAGACCAUCAUCAUCGGCGUGCGCAAGGGCGGCACGCGCGCACUGCUGGAGAUGCUCAGCCUGCACCCCGACGUGGCGGCCGCGGAGAACGAGGUCCACUUCUUCGACUGGGAGGAGCAUUACAGCCACGGCUUGGGCUGGUACCUCAGCCAGAUGCCCUUCUCCUGGCCACACCAGCUCACAGUGGAGAAGACCCCCGCGUAUUUCACGUCGCCCAAAGUGCCUGAGCGAGUCUACAGCAUGAACCCGUCCAUCCGGCUGCUGCUCAUCCUGCGAGACCCGUCGGAGCGCGUGCUAUCUGACUACACCCAAGUGUUCUACAACCACAUGCAGAAGCACAAGCCCUACCCGUCCAUCGAGGAGUUCCUGGUGCGCGAUGGCAGGCUCAAUGUGGACUACAAGGCCCUCAACCGCAGCCUCUACCACGUGCACAUGCAGAACUGGCUGCGCUUUUUCCCGCUGCGCCACAUCCACAUUGUGGACGGCGACCGCCUCAUCAGGGACCCCUUCCCUGAGAUCCAAAAGGUCGAGAGGUUCCUAAAGCUGUCGCCGCAGAUCAAUGCUUCGAACUUCUACUUUAACAAAACCAAGGGCUUUUACUGCCUGCGGGACAGCGGCCGGGACCGCUGCUUACAUGAGUCCAAAGGCCGGGCGCACCCCCAAGUCGAUCCCAAACUACUCAAUAAACUGCACGAAUAUUUUCAUGAGCCAAAUAAGAAGUUCUUCGAGCUUGUUGGCAGAACAUUUGACUGGCACUGAUUUGCAAUAAGCUAAGCUCAGAAACUUUCCUACUGUAAGUUCUGGUGUACAUCUGAGGGGAAAAAGAAUUUUAAAAAAGCAUUUAAGGUAUAAUUUAUUUGUAAAAUCCAUAAAGUACUUCUGUACAGUAUUAGAUUCACAAUUGCCAUAUAUACUAGUUAUAUUUUUCUACUUGUUAAAUGGAGGGCAUUUUGUAUUGUUUUUCAUGGUUGUUAACAUUGUGUAAUAUGUCUCUAUAUGAAGGAACUAAACUAUUUCACUGAAAAAAAAAAAAAGAUUUUUUCUGGAGACGCUAUGUUUUUUUGAAUAUAAUUAACUUGCCCCCAACUCAAAAUAGCUGUCUGUGUUGCAAUCAUUGCAAAAUCUAAAUUCUUUUGUUACUUAAAAAAACAUGUUUUUCAUGGCUAUUACAAUCCUCUCUCUCCCCUCUCCUUUCUGCAUUGCUCUUUUUAAUUUUUAAUGUCUCAUUGUGAUCAUCAGAUUUAUUUUUACUUGGAUUGUAAGAUUUAUCUCCUCGGCGAUUCCUUGUCAUUUUUGGAGGUCACAGUUUUACUCAUUCCCAUGUGUAAACUUCAAGUAAACAAAGCAAUAUUCAGGAUGGAGAAGCAGUUAGUGACUGGCUAGAGGUCUCUUGGGAUCCAUCUUGACCUCAAAGAAUAUUUGCACAUGCUUCUGAUCUCAGCAGUUAUAAUAAAGAGGAUUAAACCCUUGGCCUUCAGAAUGAUCUUGGACCUGGAUACUUUGCCCCAGGUGGCAGCUGGCCUCCAGAAAGCCAAUUAGAAUAGAAAAGAGAAACUGCGAAAUCUAUGCGUGUCUUCAUCCUGUCGGUUCUGUGAAAGGCUGACUAAAAGGGUAGUAGUCUUUUGCUUAGUCUGAAAGUCUGCUUACUUCCUGAAAGACACAUUGGCAUUAUAGACAUAUAUUCCAUAUGCACUGAGACAUAAAUAUGUGUAUGUUUCAAAAUCAACUCUAAAUUUGGAGUCCUGAAUGUGAAAGAAAAAGUAAGUUCCCAAGUGUUGAAGUUAAAAAGAGAAAAGGGCAGAGUUGAAGGUAGCACCUAAGAGAACCACUGUACCUGCCCCCAGAGGAGUGGCUGGAGUUCAGUUUUACUUCUGCCCCUGAGCAGCCAGCUUGUUGGAGAUGGUCACAUAAACCCUUCUUAUCCUCAGUUUUUUCAUGCAUUCUUCAUGCAGUCAGCCUUUUACAGAAUUAAACCCAUUGGAUUUUAAUAAAAAUAAAACAUUCAUUACAGUAAAAGAGAAAAUACAAACAAGCAAAAUAAACCGGCUUCCUGACAUGGUUUAUACCGCAGGAAAAUGACAGAAAUGGACGUUAUUAAUCAUCUCCUACACUUAAGAACUCAUUGAAAUUUCUCCAAGCAACCCCAGGAUGCAGAUAUUAUUAUGGAAAUUUCAAAGAGGAGGAAUUAGGCCCAGAGAACAUGAGAAACUUGCCCAAGGUCACAUUGACUAUAAACUCAGGCUUAGAGGCUACUCAGAGCCAAAGCACAGGUUAUUUAUGUAUUUAGUUUUUACCCAACUCUUUCUGAACUCAAAAGGAAAAGCCCAGACUCAGAGCCAGUUCUUCCUGACCUGACUUAACAUUUCUUCCCAGGUGCCAAAUAUCUUCCAUCCUAAGAGGUGUGUCCCAGAUACAGGAAGGGCAAGAAGAAGCCUGCAUUUUUCUCAGCAGUGUUAUCAGGGAAGUGAGUCACCUUGGUACGUUUCAGCAGCUCCAGCCUGACCUGACCUUAGCAUGGCCUAUGCCCCACCCCAUAUCAUGAACAGAGAGCAGAGAGGAUGCCUUCCUCUUUAGAAUCCAUUGAAGUUGUCAUUAAGCCAUCAUCUCCCCCAGAGGAAGUAGCAGAAAUAUUUACAGCAGGCCCCUGGUGGACAUGGUACUUUUCAAUAGGCAGAGAGCCUCCCUCUGCAGCACAUCGUUGGAUCUUGCUUUUACCAUACUCCUUGAAGAGCUGAAGAAAUAAGAGGGCCCAGCAAGGUUAAGUCAAGUUUCCAAGCCUGUUCAGGAAUAUGGUGACUGAAAGGAAACUGCAAUGAGAGUCUCUGACUGAAGAAGAUGCUCUUUGCAAACUGCCUGUAAAUUCCUGUCCCCUGACAGGGAUGGUCUGGUAGAAGCAUGAACUGUGGAUGCAAGAGGCAGCGGGGAGGAGUGGAGGAAGACAGGACCAGCACAUGGAAUAUAAUCUAGCUGCUGGGACUGGCAUAGUCGAUGGAGGCGGUGGUCCAGUGUAAAAUGAUCAGUGAAUGUAAAUUCAAUAUGUUUUCAUUUGGGGGUGCAGAGUCGUGGCUAAAGGAAUGUUCAAAUGAGUCUACCAUGAGCAAGGGAUCAGAGGUCCUAGUGGCACUAUCUGUUCAUUCAUUUUUGGUACAACCCCAGCCAGUCAUUGAGAAGGUACACUGUGUAAGAAACCAUCACUCCAGACUUACCCAAGGUAUUUAUUGCUAGAUCUCACCAAGCACUGUCAAAUUCAAAGGAGGCCCUGUAGUAGACCCUGGGCUGUCCUUACAGGGCCAAAAUGCAGUGACUCAGGAGCCUAAUAGCACCCGGUCCCUCCAAAACAUGCCUUCUACCAAUUCCAUUAACAGAGACAGGUGUCAGUGGAAGGGGUGGGUCUCCUGUCCAGACCACCCCGGCCCGGGAGCAGCCUGGGGGAUCUAGGUGGGUCCUUCCAGAGAGGCAAGUGAGAACAACUGAACCAAGCCUCAGCUAUUAGAUUUGGAAUAUUCACACACUUGACACUCCAGAGUCAGAACAGCCCCUUCCCUUUCCCUUCCUCCUGGAAUCAGAUAGGGUUGAAAUCCUUUUAACACCAUUUGGUUAUCAGCUCACAACCUGAAGGUUUGCAAGUUUAGGAAAAGUGACAUGCCUCUGAGCACAGGGUGCUUUACUCCUUCUGUGCUUGGAGGCUUACCCAACUGAAAGGAGAUGGAGGGCAGGAGAGGCCGAUGCCUAGCGUGCCUGCUGCUUACAGGGGUGGUGUCACAGGUCACCAUUAUUCAUUAAAAUUUUACUUUUUUGAUCCCCUACCACAUGCUCAACAUGGUAUUGAGUCCUCAAGAAUAUAAAAAGAAAAUACAACAGGAACCAGUAGUCAUUAACUGUUUGUUCUGGACUUUAAUAAAAGUACAGAGGGUCUUGGAGUACAAAGGCAAAGACAUUUAGCUGUGUAUAGAAUGGGUGGGGGAAUGUGUUCCAUGGUUUGGCAUUCAGUUCAGCAACAUUCCUGAGAGAAAUCAACUAGCCCCCUUAUAGAGAAGAGGAAACUGAGAUUUAAAAAGUGGUCCUGGCCGGGUGUAGUGGCUCACGCCUGUAAUCCCAGCACUUUGGGAGGCCAAGACAGGUGAAUCACGAGGUCAGGAGUUCAAGACCAGCCUGACCAACAUGGUGAAACCCCAUCUCUACUAAAAAUACAAAAAUGUGCCAGGCAUGGUGGCGAGUGCCUGUAAUCCCAGCUACUCAGGACACUGAGGCAAGAGAACCACUUGAACCUGGCAGGUGGAGGUUGCAGGGGGCCGAGAUGAUGCCACUGCACUCCAGCCUGGGCAACAGAGCAAGACUCCAUCUCAAAAAAAAAAAAAAAAAAAAAAGAUAAAUUAAUAAUAAAAAAAUAAAAAAGUAAUCCUGACUUCAAGUCAUUUUUUUCAGAAGAAAGGAUUCUUGCUCACUCCAGGGAAAUAGUCCAGAAAUGGAAAAUGUUGACAUCACAAAUCACAAAAGAAGGUGAAAAAUAUCAGAGACCCUCUCCAGAAUGUCAUUUCUCAGAAAUAUUAAGAAAUAGAGAAUCUUCCCAGAGGUCGCAUGUCAGGGCAGGUCACUUAACUUGUGGGCCACAGAGACCCUGACCUUCCUGUGGGAAGGCUUCAUGGAGGAAUUGCCAUAAAGCUGGGGCACGCACGAAUGGCAGUAGUGUCACCAGAGCAGGGCAUUCUGAACAAGGGAAGCUUGAGACAUGAAGACAGUGGUCACGGGGAGAGGCUGGGGGUAGAGGGUAGAGGUAGGCAAGAGAUUUGUCUGAGUGGCAUGUCAAAUGUGUUAAACUCAAUGAGAAGCUACUGCUUUCCAAGGCUGGAGUGUUGGAAGCUUACUUAGCAGGCACCCAUGUGAAUUUGGCUCCUGUGCAGGUGUAUCUGUUGCAUAAAAAUAGCUAUCAUUUGUUGCACACCUGCCAUGUGCUUGGUAUUUUAAAUAUAUUGCUUCUAACCUAUAUAACAACCCUAGGAAGUAGAAAAUGGGCUACUAAUUUUACAGAAAAAUAAACUCAGAAAUUAAAGGGCUUGCCCAUGUUGAUAGAGCCAUUACUUCUUACAAAUGAAAUUUUGUCUCCGAUGUCUCUGCUCCUUUUCAGUCCAUCUAUUUGUGGGUAAGUGGAGGAAGAUAUAAAGCAUAUGCAUCUGUCUAUUAGGCAGAGCCUGUAAGGGAAAUUAUGGGCAUCUAGGAUUUGGAGUUGGACAGUUAGGGUGAUAUCAAGAUUACCUUCAAGCAAAGCAGUGGCUGGGAUUUGAUGCAACAGGGACGUGAUAAAACAUGCUCCUAACCGGCAGCAGCUCAUUUCGGAAGACUGAGCCUGAGUUAAAGGCCAGAGCAACAUAACAGAGUUCUCCAAACAGCACACAGUGAGAGAAGGCCAAAGCUAAAGAGGACAUCAUCGGAUUUAGCUGCUUCACUAAAGUGUUUUGAUGUAGAAAAUGACCUUGGUGCUUUAGUUAUCCCUGAUGUCAAGACCUUUACUCUAUUUUGCCCAAAUUUCUCAGUUAGAUAACAGCAAAGAGAGAGAGCCAGAAGACCUGGGUGUGCAUCCUAGCUGUACCAAUCACUGACCAUGGGAUCUUAGAUUCAGACUCUGAGAACCUCCAUUUCCUUCUCCAUAAAAAUGGGCAGAUAUGUACUGUACUCUGUUGGGGGAAAACUCCAACUCAAUGAGAUAAAGUAGGUAAAAACUAUAAACCCAGUGCAUAUGUUACUUAGUGGUUAAAAACAUUUGGGACUUUAGGAGACAGACCAAAACUGGUUUUGAACCAGUCGGCAGAAAUGCGCUGCCUUUUUUCCUCCUCUGCUUCCCAGCUAUGUGACUGUAGCUAUUGCUGUUAAUGCUCCAUCCAGAGCUCAUUUACCAGGGAAGUGCUCUCAACCCCAGCUGCCACAAAGAUUGUCUUCUGUACUAUUUUCUGAAGGAUUUCUCUUAGUUGGCAGGAGUUUUCUUACCUGAAGAUGCCUGAGAAAUGUUGUCCACCCCACUCCCCUGCUUUCCUAGGGUUAGGGCAUGACUAAUGAUUGACUGACCCAUGUGGGAUGGGGCAUGGGGGUAGUAGGGUAACAGUCCACCCUCAUUGCCUCCAGGCAGGACAACCUCUGGUGCAACUCAUGCUCAGAGCUCCUCGUGAGAUCAGGCUGAGGCUAGACUUCUCCUGAAACUGUACUUUUACUUAUUUCUUCCGAAACUUCAUCCUUUUCCCACAUUACCUUACUCAUUUCUUCUGCUACCCUAUUCUCAGUAAAUGUGUUUCCCAAGAAAACAGGAAUCCCCCCUCAGACUUUGCUUCUAGACCAUCCACUCUAAAGUCUUAACCUUGCAUGCAUGUUUUCUUCUCUCUGUAUUUUACAUGUAUAACGUGAUCAACCCACGGAGUUAUUAGAAUUCUUCCAAUUAAAUGAGAUAUAGCAGAGAAUGAGUCUAUUUUAUUGGCUAGCAAAUAGCAAAGUGUUAAAUUCAAUAAUGGCUGAAAUUGUUACCAAGUAGUAGGCUCUUUUAUUAGCUUAUCGGACUACCAAAAUAGUAUAAUGCAUCAAUAUCAAACUUAAAUUUCAACUUCAUAAAACAAUUCUGGGCCCAACAAAUAUGAAGGUAUUGCUCCAUCUUAUGUAGCAACAUCUUGUAUUUCUAUUGUUUGAUAAAUAUUCCACUUAGAACUAA